CCUCUCCGGGAUUCCUUUCCCGGGGGCAGUCUCUUUUCUCUCCUCACCUGACGGCUCCCCUCCGCGCCUCCGGGGGCUCCCUCAGGCCUCCCCACGGUCAUUUCAGCUGGACAGAGGCAGCAGCGACAGUGACAGCGAUAGUGGCAGCAGCGGUGGCAGCGAGAGCUAUGCGGGGCCAGGGUCCACCCCUUUCUAGCUUUGGCGUCUGGUUGGCUUCCAGGGCAGCCUCCGAUCCAUCCCGCCCGAGGAGGCAAGGAUAUGAUAUUCACUUUCAUGACAAGAAAAUCCUGUUGCUCGAAGCAGGUCCAAAGAAAGUACUGGAGAAAUUGUCAGAAACUUACAGCAACAGGGUCAGCUCCAUUUCCCCUGGCUCUGCAACGCUUCUCAGUAGUUUUGGUGCCUGGGACCAUAUCUGCAACAUGAGAUACAGAGCCUUUCGGCGAAUGCAGGUGUGGGACGCCUGCUCAGAGGCCCUGAUAAUGUUUGAUAAGGAUAAUUUAGAUGACAUGGGCUAUAUCGUGGAGAAUGAUGUCAUCAUGCAUGCUCUCACUAAGCAGUUGGAGGCUGUGUCUGACCGAGUGACGGUUCUCUACAGGAGCAAAGCCAUUCGCUAUACCUGGCCUUGUCCAUUUCCUAUGGCCGACUCCAGCCCUUGGGUUCAUAUUACCCUAGGUGAUGGCAGCACCUUCCAGACCAAAUUGUUGAUAGGUGCAGAUGGUCACAACUCCGGAGUACGGCAGGCUGUUGGAAUCCAGAAUGUGAGCUGGAACUAUGACCAGUCUGCUGUUGUGGCUACUCUGCAUUUAUCAGAGGCCACAGAAAACAACGUAGCCUGGCAGAGAUUUCUUCCCUCUGGGCCUAUUGCUCUGCUCCCGCUCUCAGACACCUUGAGUUCCUUGGUUUGGUCCACGUCCCAUGAACAUGCAGCAGAGCUAGUUAGCAUGGAUGAGGAAAAAUUUGUGGAUGCCGUUAACUCUGCCUUUUGGAGUGAUGCUGACCACACGGACUUCAUCGACACAGCUGGUGCCAUGCUGCAGUAUGCUGUCAGCCUUCUGAAGCCCACUAAGGUCUCGGCUCGCCAGCUGCCCCCAAGCGUAGCCAGGGUGGAUGCCAAAAGCCGAGUUCUGUUUCCUCUUGGGUUGGGACAUGCUGCUGAGUACGUCAGGCCUCGGGUGGCGCUCAUUGGGGAUGCAGCCCACAGAGUCCAUCCGCUUGCAGGACAGGGUGUCAACAUGGGCUUUGGGGAUAUCUCCAGCUUGGCCCAUCACCUCAGUACGGCAGCCUUCAAUGGGAAGGACUUAGGUUCCGUGAGCCACCUCACAGGUUAUGAAACAGAAAGACAGCGUCACAACACUGCUCUUCUGGCUGCUACAGACUUACUAAAAAGGCUCUAUUCUACCAGUGCCUCCCCGCUUGUGUUGCUCAGGACGUGGGGCUUGCAGGCCACAAAUGCAGUGUCUCCACUCAAAGAACAGAUUAUGGCCUUUGCAAGCAAAUGAGUACUCCUCUCCUAAAGAAAGAUUACGUUGAUGAAAAAGAACAUCCUGCCCAGGACCCAUCAUACAUAUUUUCAAGAUCUUAUUUAAUUUAAUAAACUUACUUUACAUUAAAAUUCUCUUUUUCUUCUUUGCUUAAUGGGCCUGUGGCACCCAAAUAAUGAAUGAUAAUUUGCUGUGAGGAGCGUAUAUUAGCCAGACCAAAGGAAAAAACUUCGAAGGAAGACUUACAAUUUGGUUGAAAAGAGCUUUUUAUUACUAAAAAACCCACAAGGUGCUGUCUCACUCAUUUCCAGUUAAUCAUUUCUAAAGAGAAAAUUUACAUUUUGUUUUUGUUUUAAUGUUGGUCAUAAAUUUAUACAGUUGUUUUUUGAUAGAGGUAAGAAUUAGACUCGAUGCAUUUUUGUUAGAAUUGCUGUUUAAAUGUUAACAUCAGAAUGCAAAUUAAAUAUAAAUUGCUUUAACCUUUGUUACAGGUAUACUGGACUUUCUGAAAGGAAAACCAGGUCUCAUUAAUGCUAGUUAUUACUUUAUCACAGCACCAGAUUUCCAUUUUAUUUAUGGUUCCUCUCUGGGACACCACUGUCGGUUUAAUAAAACAAUAAAUAAUUCAUUGCACAGAUCCGAAGACCUCAGGAACCAGAUCACAAGGGAAACCGAUUAGCAGCAGAAUU